AAUGGCAGGGCGCGGUGCGGCGCGCCGAGGUGGGACGGCGGCGCGCUGAGGAGGCGGUGCGCUCAGGCGGCGCUCCCGGAGAUGCCCCGCGGCAGCCGCGCUCGGGGCUCUAAGAGAAAAAGGAGUUGGAAUACAGAAUGCCCAUCCUUUCCAGGAGAAAGACCACUGCAGGUCAGAAGAGCAGGUCUCAGGACAGCAGGGGCAGCUGCCUCUCUCUCUGAAGCAUGGCUCAGGUGUGGAGAAGGGUUUCAGAACACUUCUGGGAAUCCGUCAUUAACAGCUGAAGAGAAGACGAUUACAGAAAAGCACCUUGAAUUAUGCCCUAGACCCAAGCAAGAAACCACCACAUCUAAAAGCACCAGUGGGCUUACAGACAUAACAUGGAGCUCCAGUGGAAGUGAUUUGUCGGAUGAAGAUAAGACACUUUCUCAGUUACAGAGAGAUGAAUUACAGUUUAUCGACUGGGAGAUUGACAGUGACAGGGCAGAGGCUAGUGACUGUGAUGAAUUUGAAGAUGACGAGGGUGCUGUGGAAAUCUCAGACUGUGCUUCUUGUGCAAGUAAUCAGUCUUUGACAAGUGAUGAGAAGCUGUCGGAGCUUCCCAAGCCAAGUUCUAUAGAAAUUUUAGAGUAUUCAUCAGAUAGUGAAAAAGAAGAUGAUUUGGAAAAUGUCCUACUCAUUGAUUCAGAAUCCCCUCACAAAUACCACGUGCAGUUUGCAUCGGAUGCAAGACAGAUUAUGGAGAGACUGAUAGAUCCAAGGACAAAAUCAACAGAGACCAUUUUGCAUACACCUCAGAAACCCACAGCUAAGUUUCCCAGGACUCCAGAAAAUUCAGCAAAGAAGAAGCUUUUAAGAGGUGGACUAGCAGAAAGACUAAAUGGACUGCAGAAUCGAGAGAGAUCUGCUAUUUCUUUGUGGAGACAUCAAUGUAUUUCUUACCAAAAGACACUUUCAGGUAGAAAAUCUGGUGUAUUAACUGUGAAAAUUUUAGAGCUGCAUGAGGAAUGUGCCAUGCAAGUUGCCAUGUGUGAGCAGUUAUUGGGGUCACCAGCCACCAGCUCCUCCCAAAGUGUGGCUCCCAGGCCUGGAGCUGGCCUGAAAGUUCUCUUCACCAAGGAGACUGCAGGCUACCUCAGGGGCCGUCCCCAGGACACUGUCCGGAUCUUCCCUCCCUGGCAAAAACUGAUUAUUCCAAGUGGAAGUUGCCCUGUUAUUCUGAAUACUUACUUUUGUGAGAAAGUUGUUGCCAAAGAAGAUUCAGAAAAAACUUGUGAAGUGUACUGUCCGGACAUACCCCUUCCAAGAAGAAGCAUCUCUUUGGCCCAGAUGUUUGUAAUUAAGGGUCUAACAAAUAAUUCACCUGAAAUCCAGGUUGUGUGUAGUGGUGUAGCCACUACAGGGACAGCCUGGACCCAUGGGCACAAAGAAGCAAAACAGCGCAUCCCAACCAGCACUCCCCUGAGGGAUUCUCUCCUGGAUGUGGUGGAAAGCCAGGGAGCUGCCUCGUGGCCAGGAGCUGGAGUCCGAGUGGUGGUGCAAAGAGUGUAUUCUCUUCCCAGCAGAGACAGCACCAGGGGUCAGCAGGGGGCCAGCUCAGGACACACAGACCCAGCUGGAACUCGAGCCUGCCUUCUGGUACAAGAUGCCUGUGGAAUGUUCGGUGAAGUGCACUUGGAGUUCACCAUGUCGAAGGCAAGACAGUUGGAAGGGAAGUCUUGCAGCCUGGUGGGAAUGAAGGUUCUACAGAAAGUCACCAGAGGAAGGACAGCGGGGAUUUUCAGUUUGAUUGACACCCUGUGGCCCCCAGCGAUACCUCUGAAAACACCUGGCCGCGACCAGCCCUGUGAAGAGAUAAAAACUCAUCUGCCUCCUCCAGCCUUGUGUUACAUCCUCACAGCUCAUCCAAAUCUGGGACAAAUUGAUAUAAUUGACGAAGACCCCAUUUAUAAGCUUUACCAGCCUCCAGUUACCCGCUGCUUAAGAGACAUUCUCCAGAUGAAUGAUCUUGGUACCCGUUGCAGUUUCUAUGCCACGGUGAUUUACCAAAAACCACAGCUGAAGAGUCUGCUGCUUCUGGAGCAAAGGGAGAUCUGGCUGCUAGUGACCGAUGUCACUCUGCAAACGAAGGAGGAGAGAGACCCCAGGCUCCCCAAAACCCUGCUGGUCUAUGUGGCCCCCUUGUGUGUGCUGGGCUCUGAAGUCCUGGAGGCACUCGCUGGGGCUGCCCCUCACAGCCUCUUCUUCAAGGACGCUCUCCGUGACCAGGGUCGGAUUGUUUGUGCUGAACGAACUGUCCUCUUGCUUCAGAAGCCCCUUUUGAGUGUGGUCUCUGGUGCAAGUUCCUGUGAGCUGCCUGGCCCGGUGAUGCUCGACAGCCUGGACUCUGCAACACCUGUCAACUCCAUCUGCAGUGUUCAAGGCACUGUGGUUGGCGUGGACGAGAGCACUGCUUUCUCAUGGCCUGUGUGUGACAUGUGUGGCAACGGGAGAUUGGAACAGAGGCCGGAAGACAGAGGCGCCUUUUCCUGUGGGGACUGCUCCCGGGUGGUCACAUCUCCUGUUCUCAAGAGGCACCUGCAGGUCUUCCUGGACUGCCGCUCAAGACCGCAGUGCAGAGUGAAGGUCAAGCUGUUGCAGCGCAGCAUUUCCUCCCUGCUGAGGUUUGCCGCCGGUGAAGAUGGGCUCUAUUCACAGUGGCUGAUCAGGUCUUUACUGCGGAUCUGGAAAGAAGCUGAUAGAAGAUGGGUGCCAGAGGGGCCUGGGUAGAGAUGUUAGCUGAGAGAUACCCAGUAUGGAUUCUGUCAGUUUUCUGGAGCUACGAAGUGAAGAGUGUCCUCGGAAAGGAAGUGGGGUUGUUAAAUUGUUUUGUCCAGUCCGUAACCGCCCACCCGACCAGCUGCAUUGGAUUGGAGGAAAUCGAGCUUCUGAGUGCAGGAGGGGCCUCUGCAGAACACUAGCGGUUGCCGCAGGAUCUGUGAACUUUGCAAUGUGGCUGCAAGGGUGGUGGUGGUGGUGGUGAUUUGGGGUAGUUAUUUGUUAACUAUGGACACAGUGAACGUAGUUUACGAUCUUGAAAUGAAACUUAGAUUUUUCUGGGGAAAUGUUCAGAUACAGUUUUGUGAACUGUAAAUCAAAAUACCUUUUUCUACAGUUUAUCUUUUAUUUUCUGCAAAUUUAGGAACAUAUUUACUCGUUUUCACAUUGAAUCUUAAGUUUAAGCUCUUCAUUUGGUAUUUAGGCAAUAUAUGAGAAAAAAAUUUUUUUUGUUCAUUUGUAAUUUUAACAAGUUGAACAUUUUACCAUGAUUGAACAUGUUUUUAUUACAGUAUUUAACAUUCCCCCAAAGAAUACCCUGCAAAGUGUAAACCUUUGUCCCAUACUGUGAUAUUACUGUUCUGCUACAAUAAAUGUCAAACCUAAGCACUUUGCAGUUCACUACUUUUGGGAAAAUGUUCUAGGGAACUGUAUCACAGGUGAAACUGUUACCCAUAAAGUGUAGCUCUCUGAACUGGUGUGAUCGUGUCUCUGCUGAAUGGUGGUGGGGAUAGCUGGCUCCACCACACACACCUGUUUUAAUUAGGCUGGGUAAUGUGCACGGAGAGCAAAGAUCACAGACUAAGGAGCAGUCAGUCGGAUAUUUGCUUUGCUGGCAAAGAUUUAAACCAAGAAUUAAUUAUCUUUGGACACUAUAAAGAUUUUGUUCCCUUCCUUAUAGCAAUAUAAUCAUGACAGGCCAUGGUUAACUACAUCAGAUACACGUAGCAGCCGUGACCAAGACAUGGUGCCCUAAUACCAAGUGUUCUUGGGUUAAAG